CUCUUUUGGCAACAUGGCGGGCGGAGAAGCUGGGGUGACUCUGGGGCAGCCGCACCUUUCGCGUCAGGAUCUCACCACCUUGGAUGUUACCAAGUUGACGCCACUUUCACACGAAGUUAUCAGCAGACAAGCCACAAUUAAUAUAGGUACAAUUGGUCAUGUAGCUCAUGGGAAAUCCACAGUCGUCAAAGCUAUUUCUGGAGUUCACACCGUCAGGUUCAAAAAUGAACUAGAAAGAAAUAUUACAAUCAAGCUUGGAUAUGCUAAUGCUAAGAUUUAUCAACUUGAUGACCCAAGUUGCCCUCGGCCAGAAUGUUAUCGAUCUUGUGGGAGCAGUAUGCCUGAUGAGUUUCCUACAGACAUUCCAGGAACCAAAGGGAACUUCAGAUUAGUCAGACAUGUUUCCUUUGUUGACUGUCCUGGCCACGAUAUUUUGAUGGCUACUAUGCUGAACGGUGCAGCAGUGAUGGAUGCAGCUCUUCUGUUGAUAGCUGGUAAUGAAUCUUGCCCUCAGCCUCAGACAUCUGAACACCUGGCUGCUAUAGAGAUCAUGAAACUGAAGCAUAUUUUGAUUCUACAAAAUAAAAUUGAUUUGGUAAAAGAAAGGCAGGCUAAAGAACAAUACGAGCAGAUCCUUGCGUUUGUCCAAGGUACAGUAGCAGAGGGAGCUCCCAUUAUUCCAAUUUCGGCUCAGCUGAAAUACAAUAUUGAAGUUGUUUGUGAGUACAUAGUAAAGAAAAUUCCAGUACCCCCAAGAGACUUUACUUCAGAGCCCCGGCUUAUUGUUAUUAGAUCUUUUGAUGUCAACAAACCUGGCUGUGAAGUUGAUGACCUUAAGGGAGGUGUAGCUGGUGGUAGUAUCCUAAAAGGAGUAUUAAAGGUGGGCCAGGAGACAGAAGUAAGACCUGGUAUUGUUUCCAAAGAUAGUGAAGGAAAACUCAUGUGUAAAUCAAUCUUUUCCAAAAUUGUUUCACUUUUUGCGGAGCAUAAUGAUCUGCAAUAUGCUGCUCCAGGCGGUCUUAUUGGAGUUGGAACAAAAAUUGACCCCACUUUGUGCCGGGCUGACAGAAUGGUGGGGCAAAUACUUGGUGCAGUCGGAGCUUUACCUGAGAUAUUCACAGAAUUGGAAAUUUCCUAUUUCCUGCUUAGACGGCUUCUAGGUGUACGCACUGAAGGAGACAAGAAAGCAGCAAAGGUUCAAAAGCUGUCUAAGAAUGAAGUGCUCAUGGUGAACAUAGGAUCCCUGUCGACAGGAGGGAGAGUUAGUGCUGUCAAGGCCGAUUUGGGCAAAAUUGUUUUGACCAAUCCAGUGUGCACAGAGGUAGGAGAAAAAAUUGCCCUUAGCCGAAGAGUUGAAAAACACUGGCGUUUAAUUGGUUGGGGUCAGAUAAGAAGAGGAGUGACAAUCAAGCCAACAGUAGAUGAUGACUGAAGAAUACCGGUUAAAUAAUACAUUCGGAUGGAGCUGGAAGUUGCAAUUUCUCUUUAACAACCAAGGGGUUUAUUUUCAAAGCGAUAUUGGGGAAUUGAUUUCACAGUUUGUUACCUUAGUAGGUAACGGUAAGGUUAUUCUCUCUUUUUUUUUUUGGUUAUGAAAACUUAGGGACUACAAUUAGUAUAAAAAUUGGCAUAAUGUUGGAUUGAAUCUACAUUUUGGCAGAAGUUAAGCAUUCCCACAUAAUGUCAAAAUUAUACAUUAUGCAGUUUUUUUGUUUGUUUUAUUUUGUUUUGUUUUUGAGUCUGGCUUUGUCACCUAGGCUGGCAUGUAGUGGCAUGAUCUGCAAUCUCUGCCUCCCAGGUUCAAGCGAUUCUCCUGCCUCAGCCCCCCAAGUAGCUGAGAUUACAGGUGUGUGCCACCACACGGGGCUAAUUUUUGUAUUAGUAGAGACGGGGUUUCGGCAUGUUGGCCAGGCCAGUCUCUCCUGACCUCAGGGUGAUCAGCCCACCUCGGCCUCACAAAGUGCCGGGAUUACAGGCGUGAGCCACCUUGCCUAGCCCACAUCAUGCAGUUUGAAAUGAAACUUUGCCACAACCAGCCUUUGCUGUAGCACACACAUAUAUCACUGAAACUGUUCGAAAUAAAGUUUUUUUUUGUUUUUCAUGAUUCGUCUUUGAGUACCUCCAGGCUGAAGGACUGUUGUACCAGUAAAAACUUAAAGGCACAAAUUAUCCUUGAAGACCUUCUCCCUUUUCUUUGGCCCCAUAUUUUAUGUUGCUUUAUCUUUGAAAUUUUGCAUGAAAAGGAUGCAAUGAAUGGGUUCGAAUUGCAUGAAAAGGAUGCACGAAUGGGUUCGAAUGAAAUUGUCCUUUAGAGCAUGAUUACUUGUUCCCAUGGGCAAAUAAUUUUCUCCCCUUGCUCUUCCUGGCCUGAAAUACGGGAAACUAGAGUCAGAAGUUAUCUCCCUCUCCCUGUGAUGCCUUGAGAUGUUUUUCUGCAUUGUUUUAUGCCUGAAAUCCAAUAGUCUUCCUCCAUUGGAAAAUACUGUUAUACCAAAUAAUUCUAGAUGAGUAACAAAGAUCCUUCUAGGCCUUCAUUUUAUGUUUUUUCUUAACUGUUAUAUGAUUGUGACACAGAUUAUAAUAUUACUAAUUUUUGGAUGUUUCAAAAGGUCAAUAAGUAAAAGAUGUUAGAAAGC